GAGUGUGGGCGCCUCCGGGCCUCUGCGGAGCCCUGGGCAGCUCUGAGCUCGCGGAGGCGUGGCCGGUGCGCGGGGCCCGCGGCGCGCGGGGAUGGGGGUCUCGGUGGAUGUGCACCAGGUGUACAAGUACCCCUUCGAGCAGGUGGUCGCCAGCUUUCUCCGAAAGUACCCCAACCCCAUGGAUAAAAAUGUCAUCUCAGUAAAAAUCAUGGAGGAAAAAAGAGAUGAAUCAACAGGGGUCAUCUACAGAAAGAGGAUUGCAAUCUGUCAGAACGUGGUUCCAGAAAUUUUAAGGAAGGUGAGCAUUUUGAAAGUACCUAAUAUCCAAUUAGAAGAGGAGUCAUGGCUCAAUCCUCGGGAAAGAAACAUGGCCAUACGGAGUCACUGCCUUACGUGGACACAGUAUGCAUCCAUGAAGGAAGAGUCUGUCUUCCGGGAAAGUAUGGAAAACCCAAAUUGGACAGAGUUCAUUCAAAGAGGCAGGAUUUCAAUCACAGGGGUUGGAUUUCUCAACUGUGUUUUAGAAACUUUUGCCAGCACAUUCUUACGACAGGGAGCCCAGAAGGGAAUUAGAAUCAUGGAGAUGCUGCUAAAGGAACAGUGUGGUGCCCCCUUAGCUGAAUAAAGAAUCAUCACUUAUAAAUGGGGAAAUAAAGACUGGAAAAUGUAUGUGAUUUGCUCAACAUCAAACAGUCAUCAAGAGCCUGUGUUAACAUCUGGCGUGGAUCCAAAACCCAUGUUCUUUACCGUGGUAAGUUGUUGCAAAGCAUUCUUUGAAAAAGAUGGAAGCCUUCUUCACUCAAAAUUGAUUAAUUUCUUCAAACACUUGACCUCCCAUGAAUACCAAGUCCAUGUUAUACUCAUGGUAUAUUUUAGUGUACUUAAGGUACACACAGUAAAAGAAAUUUAAAUUUCACAAUUUAGCACAGAUAGUUGGUUGCUGUGAAUGAAAAUGUUUCUUUUUGUGCGAAUGAGUUUAUAUGUGUUAUCCUAGGUUCCUUAAAAAAAGGUAGGUCAGAUUCCAAAGAAACUGUGUUCUAGAAAAUAAUAGUUUAAUGAAAAUCUAGGUUGUGGCCCACAGAAUUGUGACUCUAUACUUAUCAGACCAGAGAAUGAUGAUUCAGGCUUAUAACUAAAGAUCCUUGAGUGUUUUUGAGGGAUUUACACCUGGGUUCUUAUAUCGUGUCUCCUCUGUAAAUCUAGCAGGAAGACAAGGAAAUUGUUCUGUACCAUUUCACCACUGAGGAAACUGAGUCUAGAGGAGUUACAUUUUCUGCUGAAGAUCACAUAACUAGGGGAACUUGUUUCUACCUCCAGACAAUUUUCUGCUGUGACCCUAAGGUAGUAGGCAUAAAGGGCUGGGGGCUAUUCCUCAAGCUAAUUUGUGGAUAAAGAUUUAUUUUUCUUCUAGGCCUUAGGAUUAUAAUGGGAAAGCUUUCUCCUCCUGUAUUCAUCUUUAAUGUAAUUAGUAUAAACUGUGAGUCAGAAGGCUGGGUUUCAGUCCUGCUCUGUCACAUACCAACUGAUAAACUAGGUCACUUAACCUAUCUGGGGCUGUGUUUCCUCUUGUGAAAAAUGAAGAUAAUAGUGCUUAUCAUUCUUGUCCUAUGGGGCUGUGGAGAGCAUCUAACCAGAGACUGUAGGUGGUAAGAAAGUGGUCUCAGCAUUCAAGUCCUGGACAAGCUCUAGCCACCCAGCAUAACCUCUUCUUUCUUAAUCAUACCAUAAUUUUCUUUUGAAGAAUUGCUUAUCUUCUGUUAUGUGUGAUCUUGGAGGGGCUGUGAAUCAGGGUCUUUCUGCCUUCCUACUACAGUCGUCAAAAAUGUUCUGGAGGCCAUUGCAAGCUUCUCCCUCCACACCCCUCCUCACCCUCUGGCAUAGUCACAGGGCAAACACUGGAUCUAAGCCAAUCAGAUGGGCUCUUUCUUCUGGAACUGAAUCCUCAGCAGAAUGACAAAGAAAGACUAAACAAUGAUGACUCAAAUGAAUUGAUCCUUUGAUUCCACAUCAGCUCCUUCAUGAGACUGGGAAGCAGUUCCUUUACCUUCUUUGUUGUCCCAUUGUGGAGCUGGCUCCUCCAGCUCUCCCAGCAAUUCUAUGGGAAUCAUUCUCCAGUGAUUUCUCUUUUUGGAUGGCCUAAGUUGGAUUAUGUUGAUUGCAAUCACAGAAUUGUAUUACAUAUGUCAGUUUUUAACGUAUUUCCUUAACCUUAAAAUGCCACAAAUUUAAUAUGCAUCAUUAAGUUUUUCAGGGAAAAAGGAAGAAGCAGUCACACUAUAUUCAAUAUAUACACCGAUAGGCAAGAGGCAUACUGGUUUGAGAAAUGUGAAACAUGAGAAGUAGAAUGUAAAAAAAAAAAUGUGUGUGUUAGAAUUGAGGAAUUAUGGUACCCAUAUUAUCAUUAUUAAUAAAUUAUAUUAGAAUAGUAGUUAUGACAACUGAGUAUUUUAUGUACCUAGAACCCACAAGGAGUCAGGGAAGUAGGCCAAAGGACAAAGGAGUUGAUUCUAAAAUUCUCUUGAUUGCUUCUCUGAGAACUUCUCAAUUUAUUCCCCUUUUGGUAUAAGAAAUAUCUGGUUUUGACUGCCAGCUAAUUUCCAGAAGUUGAAGGCAGUUAUGGUUUAUUGUGAGUGGGAGGUUUGUAAGAAAAUAGCAGUGCAGCAGUAAGGAGAAGCUCUCUGAAGUUGUUCUGAAUGUACAGCUAAUGGGCAGUUAUCUAUGAGAGAGAUUUUUAUAGCUUCCUCCAUAUAGCUGGUGAAAAGUUAGCCUGGAUGUUGGGGGAGGAGCCUGUCAAUUUGGCUUCUUAUCAAACUCAACUUUGUUAAGCAGUUAAUUCUAAGGUGUUUUAUCCACUUAUUACUAAGGCAUGUAAGUCUGAGCUGGCAGCCUUGAUUAAUAGAUUAAUGAUCACUGCUCCCUACAAUGUAAUUGUCAUUGUGUCCCUAGAAGAACUACAAAUAUACCUCCGGGGUUAGGAUUAGGUGAGGGUGACUGUCAAGCAGCCAUAGAAGGUGUGAGGAUUUGGGACUGUUUAAAUGAAGACAAAGACAUGCCCUCAAGAAGCAAUUUUCCAAGCUGCUGUUUUGACUUGACAGUGGCAGAUACUUCAUUGGAAGAUGUUGUGAAAAUGAAAUGCAGCAGGAUCAAGAGGAGAGGGUCUAUUAGUCACUCAAAACUGACUUGUGCAGAUCUUGCAAUUCCAUUUGUAUUUCUGUCUCCCUAUCUGUAAAGCAAGAGAAAUUAUUCAUAAUUUGACUGUCAUUCAUAUCAUGCUAAGUGAUUUAGGGCUGCAUCUUCACAUGACCCAGCUUAUAACAGAUGGGCUGUAGAUUUAAUGAGGUGGUGUAUCCCUGCUCUAUCAUUUCCCAGCUCCAUAAGCAAGGGCAGUUAUGCAACUCUUUAUGUCUCAUUUCCUCAUGUGGAAAAUGAAAAUAGUAAUAACCCAUCUCAUCAUCAUUUUGUUAUAAAAAUUACCUAACUAGUGUCUGACAGGCUUAGCAGGUUACAGAGUAAGUAUUCGGUAAAUGUUAGCUACGAUUACUUAGUAGAUGGGCCUGAAGAUAUUUGUCGAUGGGUGCAAUGUAGAUGUUUUAUGAUUCCUGUUAGCAUGAGUUUGAAAAACUACAGCCCUGAGUCAAAUCUAGCCUGUCACAUGUUUUUGUAGAGAAAGUCUUAUUGGACCACAGCCAUGCUCUCUUGUUUAUAUAUUGUCUAUGGCUUCUUUUUUGCUACAGAAGGAGAGUCAAGUAGUUAAGACAGAGAUCCUAAAAUAUUUACUAUCUGGCCCUUUAGACGAAAAGUCAGCCAAUCUCUGGGGAUCAUCAAGAAAACAGACAACUGUCCCACCCUUCGUGUGAUUUACGUUUAGUAAUAGAUUGGAUGUGUUAUAGUUUACUUAACUUUUCCCCUUCGGGUGAUUAAUAGACAUUUAGCAGGUUUUCAUUAUUUUCAUUCACAAAUAAUUCCACAAUAAAUGACAUAAUAUAUAUGUGAAUAUAUCUGUAGGAUAGAUUCCUACAUGUGAAACACUUAGGGGAAUUAUUUGGGACACCUCAGCUGAUGUCUUGCAGAUUUACUGAUGGGACAUUGUGAAAUUUCUCAAUACCAAAGAUGUCAGAACUAAGUACAGAAUUAAGCUGUCAGUUCUAAUUCCCUAUAACAGAGUUUAUCAGUAAUUAGCUUCUUUGAUCGAGCCAGAGGUUGCAGUCCCUAAAGAGAAAAACACAGCACUGAAUCUCAAGAAAUUGACUACUUGUCAGAUGAAGUUAACUAUCAAGAUUCCUACCCAUCACAAGUAAUCUUACAGCUGGUCAUUGCUUCCAUCUAUCAGUUCGGUGUCGCUGCCUUUUUGCUUUGGAAUAGAUUGUGUGGAUAGAGUCAUCAAGCUUAAUGGAAGUUUCCAUCUGGAUCAUGGCAUCUGUUAACCUUAAAAAGGCUUAUGAACUCUGAGUAAGGGAGCAGUUACAUUAUUCUUUCAUAUAAGGUGAUAUUAUUCCUAAGGCCACUCCUUUGUGAAACAUGCCUCAAUCAGAAGAUCUGAUGGUAGAAACAAACAUUUUAUCCAUAGGUAAAGGACCCUUCUGUUUUUUACUUUUGACACGCCUCAAAUUGUUGCACCUGCAAAGACAUGGCUCAGGAUUUACUACUAGUAUACAAAAUUAUGAUAUAUUGGUUAGUAGAUUGUGGAGAUUAGCUGACUAUAUCUAGAUAGUAUUUUAAGAUAACAAAAUGUUAUAUUGAAUCAGGGCACCUAAAAUGCAAAAGUCUAAGGGGCGAAGGAGAUAAUGUUAAUGGUGAACUUGAAAGCUUGUUUUUCAUUUGAAGAGAGGGGCUGCUACUUAGUCCCAGCCAAUUGCUGCCACACCUUACUUUUCUAAAAGAAGGUGGACAUACACUUCUGUAGGUAAAACUGUCCCAAGAUUUAGAAGUCUGCAACUAAAAAUAAAUUAACUUAAAAAUAAAAUAAGGACUUCAUGUCUAAAACACCAGAAGCAAUGACAACAAAAGCCAAAAUUGACAAAUGGGAUCUAAUUAAACUAAAGAGCUUCUGCACAGCAAAAGAAACUACCAUCAGAGUGAGCAGGCAACCUACAGAAUGGGAGAAAAUUUUUGCAAUCUACUCAUCUGACAAAGGGCUAAUAUCCAGAAUCUACAAAGAACUCAAACAAAUUUACAAGAAACAAACAAACAACCCCAUCAAGUGGGCAAAGGAUAUGAACAGCCACUUCUCAAAAGAAGAUAUUUAUGCAGCCAACAGACACAUGAAAAAAUGCUCAUCAUCACUGGCCAUCAGAGAAAUGCAAAUCAAAACCACAGUGAGAUGCCAUCUCACACCAGUUAGAAUGGCGAUCAUUAAAAAGUCAGGAAACAGCAGGUGCUGUAGAGGAUGUGGAGAAAUAGGAAACACUUUUACACUAUAGGUGGGACUGUAAAUUAGAUCAACCAUUGUGGAAAACAGUGUGGCGAUUCCUCAAGGAUCUAGAACUAGAAAUACCAUUUGACCCAGCCAUCCAAUUACUGGGUAUAUACCCAAAGGAUUAUAAAUCAUGCUGCUAUAAAGACACAUGCACACGUAUGUUUAUUGAGGCACUAUUCACAAUAGCAAAGACUUGGAACCAAGCCAAAUGUCCAACAAUGACAGACUGGAUUAAGAAAAUGUGGCACAUAUAUACCAUGGAAUACUAUGCAGCCAUAAAAAGUGAUGAGUUCAUGUCCUUUGUAGGGACAUGGAUGAAGCUGGAAACCACCAUUCUCAGCAAACUAUCGCCAGGACAAAAAACCAAACACCACAUGUUCUCACUCAUAGGUGGGAAUUGAACAAUGAGAACACUUGGACACAGGAAGGGGAACAUCACACACUGGGGCCUGUUGUGGGGUUGGGAGAGCGGGGAGGGAUAGCAUUAGGAGAUAUACCUAAUGUAAAUGACGAGUUAAUGACUGCAGCACACCAACAUGGCACAUGUAUACAUAUAUAACAAACCUGCACAUUGUGCACAUGUGCCCUAGAACUUAAAGUAUAAUAAAAAAAUAUAUAUAUAAAAAACAAAACAAAAUGAAACAAAGUAAAUAAAUUAACUUUAAAAUAAACUUGAAAAUAAAUAACUUAAAAAUAAAAAAGCAUAUAUGGCAUGACAGUUGAAAUAUAUCUGCUAGUUUGAUACCACCUGUAAGCCAAAAAAAAAAAAAUCUGUAAAGUCAGGCGGUAGAAUGAUUGAGAAUAGAAAUGGCUCAGGAUGAGAUGCUCACAAUUAAGGCCAUGAAUUGCUAGGAAUUCCCCUUAAGAAACAGUGCUUUGUCAUCAGACUUAUCUACCAGCAGGGUAACUUCUGUUUCCUUCUUGAGGACUAAAUGAUAAAAUGUAUGUAAAGUACUUUGCACGGUCUCUGAUACGUGGUAGAUACUAAAUAUAUAUUAGCUAAUGUAACAUAAAAUGUAAAAUGGACCUACAUUUUAUUUUAAAAAUAUGAAAUAUACUUUAGGUCUAGAAUCCUUUCAUUCUUUUUUUUAGGAUUAGCAUAUAUGUAGACUUGGAAUGGUUUGUCAUAUCCCUAUUUCCUGGAGAGCCACUAUGAAAUCCUUCAGUGUUGUCGUUUUAUGACUGGACUUGUGAAGGGCCCAGAAAACUCUGUGUGGUGUAUCAGGUGCCAGAGCACUGGGAAUUCCAUGAUGCAGAUGGAGGCUUCCAGUGCUGGUGGGCUAGAGUUGUGUUCUGUCCCUAAGGACAAAUACUCUUGGUUAUAACAGUGAUUCUCCAGAUUUUUAUAAGUUAUGGAUUGUCAUGAUAACCACUGGGAUAGUGGACUGAACCAGAAGGACUGUGAAGUAUGUUUUAAUGUGGAAAGGGUCUUCCUGGGUUUUACAAACUUCUGGGAAGAUACUCCUGGGAGAUGCUCGUGGGCAUUAUAAUAUCAUCAAAGGGUCAUUGGAGACCUUUCAAAUUUACUAGUGACCCUGGUUGAGACUAAUGAGAAUGUUGAUCUAGUGCUGGUAACAUAUAUUUCUUUAGAUUUGGUACUAGAUUAAUUUUUCAUUUUUAUGGACAGGUGAAUUCAGGGUGGGUGGUAGGUGUGAGGUUGUAAUGGUAGAGGCAUAAAUGCUUGUUCUAGGUUGAGUGUGGCUUGCUAAAUGGGAGUGGGUUGGGGUUAAGAAGGCCUGGGCGGCCCUGAAAUAAGUAUUGGACUUCAUUAUUUUAGUGGCCUGCUUAGACAGAAAACUAUCAUUUCCUGGAAAAAGCCCUAUAUCUGUUUGUUACCAAAAUGUUUGUCCCAGCUUGUCAAGGGACAAUGUGUUCUUGGAUUUUCUACUCAGUGGUUUAAUUACCAGCCAAUAUCAAAAUAAAAUGGAAAUUUUACAUUCUUACUUAGUGGAUAAACUAUUUAUCUAUUGCCUUGUCCAAGCAUUUUACAUAGUUAUAGAUAGAUAUAUGAUAUGUAGGUAAAUAGAUAGACAUACAAAAACAUACAUUAUAUAUCAUGUAAUAUAUAUUCUAAUUUGACUUUAAUUACCAGCACAUAAUUUAAAUUCAUGUUAGUUUGAUCACUAUUUCCAAGUAGUAAACUAAAUGCAUAAUUGUUCAUUUAAAUUGUCACAAAGCCACCUGUUUUUCAAGACCUUUUAUUACUCAUAAUGAAAAAUGGUAUUAAUUAUUAUCAUUUGUAUCAAGAUAUUAAUCUUGCCAAAUUGGUAUGCUUAUGUUUGUAUUCAUACUUUUGGUUUCUAUAGUAAAGUGAAUUUCCUAUGGAGAGUAUCUUUUUAGAUGUUCUUAUCUGUUUUUCUCAUUCAUUUUAUUAAUCAUUGCCAACUGUUAAACUGUUCAGCUUCCAAGGACUUUUUUUUUCUUCCAUGUCUUUAAUGACUAACUUAUUUGGAACAGCAGCAGAAAGAAAAAUCUCUGAGGCAGAAUCUGCUCACACACAUUCUGACACGUCUCAGCUCAGGGAAAAUUUCCAAAGGAUAAUUAUAGAUGUCACUAAAGCUGAAUUCAUGAUGGUCAGAUUGUCAGAAAUCUUAUUUAUAAAUGCUAUCAUAAUAAUGGAGGGGAAUAUAUCUUACUUUGGAAAAGGAAAAGUUUGAAACCUUCAAGGCUGCCUGGGUUUGCCUGCAUCUCUGGCUCUGGGAUCUAGUUUUGUGUUAGAAUCACCUGUGGAGCUUUUGAAUGCUAAAAUUUAAUUCAGCCACUAACAAAAGUUUUCUCGGACAAUAUUUACUAUUAUACUAACUAGCACAGCACUCACUCACUGUUUGGCACUGUUCUAUCCACUUUAGAUCUAUCAUUAACUCAUAGAGUUCUUCCAACAAGUCUAUGAGGUAGUCACGAUUAGGACGGUUAUUUUACCAAUGAAGAAAUGGAGACAUGGAAAAGUUAAGUAGCUUGCCCCGGGGUCACAUCAGUAGUAAGGGUAGAGUCGGAGUUAACCCAGGCAGCUUAAUUCCUGAGUUAAUGCUUUCAAUUACUGUAUCUUCCUACUGCUCAUCUUCACCAUGACUAUGACCAGAGAGAAAGAUCUGGGUUUAUUAGGAUAAUAUCACACAAUGGAAUUCAUUGCCUGGUUCUCAACUCUUACGCAUUUAAUUUGAAUACCUUAUUUGUAUCAUUAUUGACUUUUGGAUAUAGUGACUGAUUACUCUCUAAUGAGCACACACAUAAAAAUUUGUCUCUAGUCUGGACUAACUAAAUCAGAAUCUUUGAUGGGUGGGGCCUGAGUAUCUGUGGUUUAAGCAGCUUCUUUGCUGAUUCUGAUGUGCAUGCUGCUAGCCAUCUAAUAUCAGAAGGUGGAAAACUACACUAUUAAUUUCAAUAUAAAGUAGACUGAGACCAGGACUCUAGGAGGCCAUGAAAAGUACUAUGGGGGAACAGGUGGAAGGCAUUAAUUCUGAGAAGCACAUACAGUGACAUAUUUAUAUAUACUAUUAUUACAAUAGCUUUCCCAAUUCUAACCCGUUCUGAUCAAUAGGACAACAUACAUUACAAGAGGAUUUUGGGCAGAAUUUUACAUUUUUGAGGGACUUUACUUUAGGCUCUUUGGUCCAGAGGGCAAAGUCAGGUACCCCAGUCCCCCCUGUUGGCCUAUGUCAAAUAUUAAAAAUAUUAAAUCCAUGGAUUUCAUAUAUCAGAUAGGAAACCAUACCUUCUGUACCUCUUCUAAUACACAUGCUGAUUCAUAGAGAGGCUUUAAUUACCUCAAAGAAGAUGCCAACCAAUUGCCAAUUUGAUACAUCAAUUGGCAGUGUUUAAUAAAAUAAAUGAGAAAAACAGAUAAGUAACAUCUAAAAAUAUAUUCCAUACAUCUUUCACAUGUCCAAAUACAUCCAUAUAUCUCUGUCUUAAAGAGAUGACAUAUUAAAAGGUCUGUAGAAGGUGAAUACACAGUAUUAAGAACCAUUUGCUAACUAUCCCCUAUGAGAAAUGAGUUUCAUUCAAAUUCCCUCCUACAGGAUAAACCUGCAGAUAUUUGAAGACAGACUUCUUGCCUUUUUCUUAGGCAUAUAUUUCUGUUUCCUGGUGUUGAGAAAUAUUUAAACAUUAAGCUUGUCAAGGCCUAAUCUUGUGGUAUCAGAGUCCUAAUAUCAAUAAUUAACUUUCUAUUGUCAUAACAAAAUUGGCACUAAGAGAGGUAUAUAGUUGUUCCACCUUUCCCUUAUUCUAAUAUUAUUUCCUCAGUGAGCCAGGGCCUUAAAUAACUAUACAUUUGCAUAAGGGAUGCUCGAUUGCUGCAUUAGCUCUUAGGCUUUUCUCAACUCUAUCUGGAAGCAUCAUGCUUGGGGUAAUUAAAGAACCUCUUUAAUUCAGCAUGUGUUUUAGAAGACGUACAGAAGGGGCAUGGUUUCCUAUCUGAUAUAUGAGACCUGUGGAUUUAAUAUCUUUAAUAUGUGACACAGGCCUUUGGAGGUCAUUGGGGUACUUGACUUUGCCCUCUUUGGACCACAGAGCCUAAAGUAAAGCCCCUCAAAAAGGUAGAAUUCUACCCAUAAUCCUCUUGUAAUGUAUGUUGUCCUGUUGAUCAGAACAAGUUAGAAUUUGGGAAGCUGUUGUAAUAUUAAUGUGUAUAAAAGCUUUGGUAACUUUUAUCUCUGAAUCAGGCUUAGAGUAUUACGUCAUCACUGGACUUCCAUACAUAUUAAGUUACUGCCAUGUGGCAGUAGUGUUCUCUUAACUGGACUCUGUUUUCUUUUGGUUUAUCUUUGGUCUCUGUGGGAUCUUUACUGCUAAGAUGUAGAGCCUUAAUGCUGGCAAUACCUUCAGGCCCCUGUAGGCUUCUGGCUGCAUUCUGUUUGCUAUUGUCUCUAUGACAGUUUCAUGCCCAGAAUGGGUCACCAGUAGACAGUGAUUUUCAUUUGUCCAGGACCCAUAUCAGAGUCCUUCCCGUUAUGAAGUUGCAUAGGGGAACACAAUGGUCAUAAUAUGAUUAGGUAUAGUUAAUGUGACUACUUGCUCAAUGCAAAUUAAUUACAAAGUUAAACUGAAAACUAUGCAAAAGAUAUAGAAUUCUAUAAAAUUAAUUAAAAAUGAAAGUGGAGAACUUCUCCCAUCACAUGGUAAACUAUUGUAAAAGGAUUAGACAGGACCAUAUCAAUUAAAACUAAAGACACUAAAAAAAAAAAAAAAAACUUCAAAUAGGAUGCUUUGAGUUAAAAAAUGAUUAGGAGACAUCCUUUUGAAACUUAAAAAAGAUUAAAAAUGUUUUGCAAAGAUUUAUAAUUGUGAAGAAAGGUUAGACCAAAAUGAAGGAUUUUCUAUAGCAGGUCAUAAAAUUAUGUCGGUAAAAUUAAAUAAAAAACAAACAAAAAAUUAUUCUUUGUUUAUUUUGAAAAAUAUACAAAGCUGAAAUCAUAAAAUAAAUUUAGUUCCACAUAAUUAAACAAUCAUUUUAUGUUCAGUUUCAUUUUUCAACAUAAAAUUUCAAAUCAAACUUUUUAUUUAUUUAUUUUUUACUAUUUACUAUAAAAUUUUGUCUAAUUUAUAUCACUCAAGGGUUUGGCAGGAAGCAGAAGGUACAGUCAAAGCAGUCACUGGAGAGAGUUUACUAUUUUCAAAGACCUGGACAAGUUUUAAGGAACUACUAAGGGAUAAUCUAGUAACCUGGGGCUAGUAGAAGUGGAAAGUCAUCACCUCACCUAGGAUUAAGGAGCCAACUAGAAACAGCAGUCACUUGAACUCAGAAAGAGUAACCGUAUGGAGAGUGUCGCCUUCGGUAGACAGUGGGCACAGCCAACUCACAGUGAUUACACAGGGAGGAAACCAGAGCACUAAUGCUCUUCUUUCUUCUCUUUCAGCCCUGAUCUCCUGCCAGUGGCCCCAAUGGCCAAAGCCAACCUGAAGCCAGAACAUAAAUAGAUCAGUUUUCUUGGUCACAGAGCAGGGUAGGGAAAGAUGGAGAGUAGAACUGGAAGAGAAAAUGACAAAUUCCAGCAUGCCAUUUGAAAUAGAUUAAAUGACUUAGAUGUUUCUGAAUUCAUGCAAUUUUUGGACAGCUUAAAAGAAUAGGACUUGUACUGCUUGAUUUAAGACACAUUUCAAUGUAAAGUUAAAUCAGCUUUUGUAGUCACAAUAUGUACUCUUACUGAACAAUGAUUGACAUGGUAAUAUCCUUCAGAAUUCCCCAUGCAUACUGCUCCUACAUCAUGUCCUCCAAUUUUGUAUUUGGGAAGUUUUCUUUUUGGAGCUAUGUAUAAGACUUGACAUUUAUUUAAAUUAAGGUUUGUGAUAAUCAAUUUGGAUUAUGUUUCAGUCUCCUGAGAUUUUUCUGGAGUUUGACAUUUUAUUGUAUCAGUGCUCUCUGUAGCUUUUUGUCAUGCUUACGUACUAUCAGCUGCAAUGAUCAUCCAAUCCUUGAUAACGAUGCUACAUUGGGCAUGGCCGUAGGUAGAUCCCUGAAGCAUACUACUAUAGACUACACUCCAGAAUGGCAAUAAUUCAUAAUGUAUUAUUCAGGUUAGACUAGGUUGUGCUGCAAUAACAAAUGAACCUUCCAAAUCUCAGUGACUUUCCAUACCAAAGUUUAUUUUUUACUCAUGCUGCAUACAUAGUCCAUGUAUUUCUGCUCACAGUUCAGUGGUUGAACCUCGUCAUAUAUCCUCAAUCUAACCAUAAAGGAGUUAAAAAUGUGGGAGGAUACAUAAAUAUUUGAUGAGAAUUAAAUUUUAAUAUCAUUUGCAUCCAUUCCUUUGACCAAUUUUGAAUCCACCUGAUACUAAUCUUAUCUAUAUUUCUCCAUCUUUUAAUGACUUGUUAUUUAUUGAAGGCCUUUUAUAGAAUAACAAUAAUUAAACAUACACUCCAAGACCAUCCAGUGGGAUAGGAAUUAUCAUUUUCCUUAAAUAGAUGAGAAAACUAAAGAUUAGAAGUUAAGGCCGGGCACGAUGGCUCACGCCUAUAACCCCAGCACUCUGGGAGGACUAGGUGGGCAGAUCACAAGGUCAGGAGAUUGAGACCAUCCUGGCUAACAUGGUGAAACCCCAUCUCUACUAAAUAUACAAAAAAUUAUCCAGGUGUGGUGGCGGGUGCCUGUAGUCCCAGCUACUUGGAAGGCUGAGGCAGGAGAAUGGCGUGAACCCGGGAGGCAGAGCUUGCAGUGAGCAGAGAUCAUGCCACUGCACCCCCCAGCCUGGGCGACAGAGCGAGACUCCAUCUCAAAAAAAAAGAAGAAGAAGUUAAAUAUCUUGUCUGAGGGUAUACAGUCGAUGAGCAAUAAAGAUUUGAACCAAUCAAUUCUAAACAUACAUAUUGCUGCUUAUUAUCUAUAUAUCUAAUCUCUUAGCUAAAAAUGGAAUAAAAGAAAGGGUAAACCUAAGGCCAGAUUGAAAAUAGGACAAAUUGAUUUUUCAUCCUUCACAGCAAUUCUUUCCUUGUGCUCUGAUUUGUACUACUUUGUCUCGUAUUUAUACACACAAAGCUCUCAUUAUCUCCAUCCGUUAUCAAUUGCUCCCACACAAAAAUCUGAGAAGUCACUCAUAUUAAAGUAAAAAUGACUCAAUCUCUUGUUUUCCAUUUUAAGGGUUACUUACUUAUUAAAGUUAGAUCAUCCUGCCACUAAGAAUACAUUUCUAGUUUCAUAUAAAACAUCUUUGAAAUAGUUUAUUUAAGUAAACACAUAUUAUUGUUAUCCCUAAAAUUAUAUCAUGGAGCUGCCAACAGUGUGAUCUUAGGAGGCAGUAUAGCACAAUAGAAAACAUGGACUUUGGGCUCAGGAUAUGAAUUAAAUCCUUGUUAUACUUCUAUGUGACUGUGUGAAAUGUAUUUAAAUUCCUGUGACCUUAGUUUUCUCAUCUGUAAAAUGACUUAAUGCCUACCUUAUAUUUUUUGUGAAGAUUAAAGAAGUAUAGCACAGGGUAGGUGCCCCAAGUAUUUGUGAAGUGAAUGAAUAAAUGGUGUCCAGAAUACACUAAGCAAGUCUUGAUACAGAGAAGUUAGUAAAUGAUUGUAAAGUUGGAUCUAGGGCCAGGGUAGAGUAUGUUAGGAAAAGAAAGUCAGCAAGUGAAGCCAAGUAUGGAAAUUAAUAAGUGUGUUUCAACCCAAAUGAAUUAUUGUUUUGUGUCAUAGGUUUAUAUGAUAAUAGAAUAGAGGAUAAUUUAUUUUGGAAUCUACCCACUAAAAAUACAUGUUCUAUAUCUUACUACUAUAGCAACUAAAAACAAUCUGCUGUAAUAAGAUGGUGUGCAUGGUGGCAGUGUGAUUAGCCAGCGUAUGAAGAACUCUUUAUUGAAAUAACUGGCCCAACCUGAAACGUAUGGCCAGGUGGCAUGAAAAAUAAAAGAUAAUUGCAGUUGGGUUGUAGCAGUCUCACUAGUUAAUGACAUGAAUUGUGAUAACUCUUGGUCAUUUUUUAUGUUGCUGAACUAACAGGCUGGGCACAGUGGCUCAUGCCUGUAAUCCCAGCACUUUGGGAGGCCGAGGCAGGAGGAUCACGAGGUCAGGAGUUCAAGACCAGUCUGGCCAAUAUGGUGAAACCCAGUCUCUACUAAAAAUACAAAAAUUAGCUGGGAGUGGUGGCAUGCCCCCUGUAGUCCUAGCUACUUGGGAGGCUGAGGCAGGAGAAUUGCUUGAACCCGGGAGUUGGAGGUUGUGGUGAGCCAAGAUCGCAUCACUGCACUCCAGCCUGGGCGACAGAGAAAGACUCUGUCAAAAAAAAAAAAAAAAUUAAAUUGUAAUUAUUCAAAUGUUUUCUAUAAAUUCUAUUUAGGAAACUAUAGAUAAUAAAGAAAAAGUAAGAAGAUAUAGUUGAGGCAUUUUUGGGGGGACAUGAUUAUGCCUUUUCUUUUUGUUUCAAUCAUUGUACAUUUCAGAAUGAAGAUUAUUUUAAAUCUGGAAAUAUAUUUAGUAGGGGAAAUUUUAUAAUAUGAAAAAAUAAAUAUGUUAAAAUAA